GCGGCGCGGGAGGCGACCAUGCGCGGCGCGGGGGCGAUCCUGCGGCCGGCGGCGCGUGGUGCCCGGGACCUGAACCCGCGGCGGGACAUCUCCUCCUGGCUGGCCCAGUGGUUCCCUAGAACCCCAGCCAGGUCCGUGGUGGCCCUGAAGACCCCCAUCAAGGUGGAGCUGGUGGCAGGGAAAACCUACAGGUGGUGUGUGUGUGGCCGCAGCAAGAAGCAGCCCUUCUGUGACGGCUCCCACUUCUUCCAACGCACUGGCCUAUCUCCACUCAAGUUCAAGGCCCAAGAGACCCGCAUGGUGGCACUCUGUACCUGCAAGGCCACUCAGAGGCCCCCGUACUGCGAUGGCACCCACAGGAGUGAGCGCGUGCAGAAGGCAGAAGUGGGCUCCCCACUCUGAGGGGGCUGCUGCUGUCCAGCCACAGGUGGCCUUGGCUCCAGGCCUCUGACAGGCACCCCCUUCUGUGGGAAAGGAAACAGGUGCUGAGCCCAAGAGACUCUGGUACCCACUGCUGGCUCAUGAAGGAAGAAUUAUUCCUUAUAACCUAAAAGUCUCCAGUCUGGGGCAGGCGGGAGUGGGCCCUGGUUCAAUGUUUGCUGAUGGGGAAGAUGGCAAAAACAAGCCUGCCCAACCAGACUGGUAGUCCUGCAGUCACUGCUAUGAGGCCCACGUGCUGCCUCCUGCUCCAGAUUUUAACCUCUCUGUGGGCUGGGGGCACCUGACCAGCCACAGGAGAGGGCAGUUCAGAUUCAUUCUGUAUGGGGUCCCCAAGCCAGGCUAAACCCAGAGAUGAGAGGCACCCUUCCCUUCUUCCCUCCACCCCAAAGAACUACAGGCUCCAGAAAGUAUGCAGCAUUUAUUACAAAGCCAAGAGAUACAGAUGUCCCAGGGCAAAGGAGGGUACAGUCACAGGACCUCAGACACAGGACAAGGUGCAAACACAGACAAGCCCAUCAGGGGGCUCCCAACCCCACACACCUACGCUAUGAUGGAAUCUCGAGUCUCGACUCCCGACUCCUCUCAGAUCUAUGCACACUUGAGGAAAUCUCGGUGGGCAGCGACCUGCCAGGGUCUGUCCCUAAGGAGGUGGUCCGCUGACCUCUCAAGGGGUGGGGGUGGGGUCAGAGCUUACAGGUUUCUGUCUUCUUGUGCUUUUAGAUGCAGUUGCUCUGUCCUGACCAGGUGACCGGGCCUCAGCUGGGGGUGGAGGGGCAAUUGGAAGGCUGUUUGCCUCUGGCAAAGUCUGGGAUCUGUGCUUGUGUGAGGUUAACCCACCCCCACUUCCACUCUAGGCCCCAGGUGAGACUCCACCACCAGUCCUGCUAGUGAGGGUUCCCCGGUGAGGGUAAGGUUGGUGGGGGUGCAGCGCUUCACAAUGCUAAAGCCUUAGCCCUCCUCCAAGAGCUGAGACCUCUCAGGGCCUGAAUCUUCUUUUCCACAAGAUAAAUGAUGCAAAGGCCACACACACAGGAAAAAAAAAAAAAGAGGCAGAACUAUCUAUUCUUUGCACAAAGUUUCCACUGCAAGAGGAGGAGGUGAUGCAGGUGCCACCUCCACCCUGCACUUGCUCCUCAGAACCAGGGAUAAACUGCAUUUGUAAAAGGCACUGUUCUUAGCAAUUUCUGGACAUUCAACAACGUGGGGGGCGGCCACUGGUCAGAGGCAGGACAGCAGCCAAGAUGGGGAGAGAAACGGGGAGAGAAAGAAACGAUUCUAACUGACUCCUAUAUGCAGCCAGUUGGAAUCAUGCCUAAAGCUUUGGGUCUGAAGGGGCCCCCAACACACCACCUGCCUUGGGAAACAGCGAGGAUGGUGCAGAGCUUUAUUGAGACUCCAGUGGCCCAUCCAGUUCAUCUCCAGGCACCCCCAAAAACAGCAAAUUACACAAGACCCCCCCCAAAAAAAAUGAACACCAUUUUCCACACAUACACACACACAUAAAGUUUGUUUCCUGUGGCAUUUAAAUUAAUCUGGUUGGUCCAUAGAAAAUAAGUAUGUAUAUUUGGUUUUUCCUAUGUACAUAUAUAUAUAUAUUUAUUUAUAAAACCCGCCCCCCACCCCCAAGGUGGGAAGAGCUGGGGAAAGUAGAAGAGGUGGAAAAAAGGGCCCAGAAAAAGUGGAAGGAGUGGAGAGGCUUGGCUGGAAGAAGGGAGAGGGUCCCUGGCCUCAAGUUAAGGGGGGCACGGGAGCGCCGUUGACAGUCAUCUUGCGCCCCCUGCUGGUGGAGGAUGGUGUCUGCAGGCAGUUCAAGCUACCCCCGUUGGCAGCUGUGGUGGCCCCACUGGCUGUCGAAGGGGGAGUGGGGGAGGUAGGGUGGGUGGCUGGAGGCCCAUGGGAACUGGGAGAGCCAUGGGAUGGGGUGGCUGGGCUGGGCAGGGAGGAGGAGGUGGCUGGCAGGGUGGCAGGGCUGGGAGCCUUGUCGCUGACUGACUCACACUCGGACGCCCCGCUGGUGUUGGUGCCCUCGGAGGGGGUGGGCACCGUGGCUAGGGUGAGCCGCUUGCAGGCUGGCUGGACACGGUACUUGAGGGGGAGAGGCCCGUUCUGCG